GAGAGCUCCAGACCUCCCGGCUACUCAGAAGCCCUCGGACUGCCCGGACCGCGCGAUGGAGUCGACCGGCAGCGUCGGGGAGGCCCCGGGCGGACCCCGGGUGCUGGUGGUGGGCGGCGGCAUCGCGGGGCUGGGCGCGGCGCAGAGGCUCUGCGGCCACUCCGCCUUCCCGCACCUGCGGGUCCUGGAGGCCACGGCCCGCGCCGGGGGCCGCAUCCGCUCGGAGCGCUGCUUCGGUGGCGUGGUGGAGGUGGGCGCGCACUGGAUCCAUGGGCCCUCCCGGGGUAACCCCGUCUUCCAGCUGGCUGCUGAGUACGGGCUGCUGGGGGAGAAGGAGCUGUCCCAGGAGAACCAGCUGGUGGAGACCGGGGGUCACGUGGGCCUGCCCUCCGUGAGCUACGCCAGCUCCGGGGCCAGCGUGAGCCUCCAGCUGGUGGCGGAGAUGGCGACUCUGUUCUACGGCCUGAUAGACCAGACCCGGGAGUUCCUGCACGCUGCAGAGACCCCGGUGCCCAGCGUCGGGGAGUACCUCAAGAAGGAGAUUGGCCAGCACGUGGCCGGCUGGACAGAGGAUGAGGAGACCAGGAAGCUGAAGCUGGCCGUCCUGAACUCCUUCUUCAACCUGGAAUGCUGUGUGAGCGGCACCCACAGCAUGGACCUGGUGGCCCUGGCACCCUUUGGGGAGUAUACCGUGCUGCCGGGGCUGGACUGCACCUUUUCUAAGGGCUAUCAAGGACUCACAAACUGCAUGAUGGCCGCCCUGCCGGAGGACACUGUAGUUUUUGAGAAGCCUGUGAAGACCAUCCACUGGAACGGGUCCUUCCAGGAGGCAGCCUUUCCCGGGGAGACCUUUCCAGUGUCGGUAGAGUGUGAGGAUGGAGACCGGUUCCCGGCGCACCAUGUCAUCGUCACCGUGCCCUUAGGUUUUCUUAGGGAACAUUUGGACACCUUCUUUGACCCUCCCCUGCCGGCUGAGAAGGCAGAAGCAAUCAGGAAGAUAGGCUUUGGGACCAACAACAAAAUCUUCCUGGAGUUUGAGGAGCCCUUCUGGGAGCCAGACUGCCAGCUGAUCCAGCUGGUGUGGGAGGACACGUCGCCCCUGGAGGAUGCUGCCCCUGAGCUACAGGACGCCUGGUUCCGGAAGCUCAUUGGCUUUGUGGUCCUGCCUGCCUUUGCGUCUGUCCACGUUCUCUGUGGGUUCAUUGCCGGACUUGAGUCUGAGUUCAUGGAGACUCUGUCGGAUGAAGAAGUACUUCUGUGUCUCACCCAAGUGCUCCGGAGAGUGACAGGAAACCCACGGCUCCCCGCGCCCAAGAGCGUCCUGCGGUCUCGCUGGCACAGCGCCCCGUACACUAGGGGGUCCUACAGCUACGUGGCCGUGGGCAGUACUGGGGGCGACCUGGACCUGCUGGCUCAGCCCCUCCCUGCAGACGGCGCCGGCGCCCAGCUCCAGAUCCUGUUUGCGGGGGAAGCCACACAUCGCACGUUUUACUCCACGACGCACGGGGCUCUGCUGUCGGGAUGGAGGGAGGCCGACCGCCUCCUCAGUCUGUGGGCCCCGCAGGUGCAGCAGCCCAGGCCCAGGCUCUAGCUGGGCCCAGCCUACUCUGUUCCACCCGUGUCGGGGGUAGGCUGGGACCCUCAUUUCUUCUGACAGAUUUCAGUCUGGCUUGAAAUUUGGGGAUGUUAAUGAGGGUCCUCUGGUUUUUGGUAACCAGGGCCACCUUCUCAGUUCUUGUGUCUGUUAUUGGAGUCUGGCCAGGGUUGACUUGAGCUGAGACACCAGAUGCUCACGGAGAUGCUGGACACAUAAAGCAAGUUACAGCCACA